AGUCGGAUAGUUGGCGGGUGGUUGAGUAGAAGCGGUCGCCAUGUCCGCGGGGAGCGCGACACAUCCUGGAGCUGGCGGGCGCCGCAGCAAAUGGGACCAACCAGCUCCAGCCCCACUUCUCUUCCUCCCGCCAGCGGCCCCAGGUGGGGAGGUCACCAGCAGUGGGGGAAGUCCUGGGGGCACCACAGCUGCUCCUUCAGGAGCCUUGGAUGCUGCUGCUGCUGUGGCUGCCAAGAUUAAUGCCAUGCUCAUGGCAAAAGGGAAGCUGAAACCAACUCAGAAUGCUUCUGAGAAGCUUCAGGCUCCUGGCAAAGGCCUAACUAGCAAUAAAAGCAAGGAUGACCUGGUGGUAGCUGAAGUAGAAAUUAAUGAUGUGCCUCUCACAUGUAGGAACUUGCUGACUCGAGGACAGACUCAAGACGAGAUCAGCCGACUUAGUGGGGCUGCAGUAUCAACUCGAGGGAGGUUCAUGACAACUGAGGAAAAAGCCAAAGUGGGACCAGGGGAUCGUCCAUUAUAUCUUCAUGUUCAGGGCCAGACACGGGAAUUAGUGGACAGAGCUGUAAACCGGAUCAAAGAAAUUAUCACCAAUGGAGUGGUAAAAGCUGCCACAGGAACAAGUCCAACUUUUAAUGGUGCAACAGUAACUGUCUAUCACCAGCCAGCACCCAUCGCUCAGUUGUCUCCAGCUGUUAGCCAGAAGCCUCCCUUCCAGUCAGGGAUGCAUUAUGUUCAAGAUAAAUUAUUUGUGGGUCUAGAACAUGCUGUACCCACUUUUAAUGUCAAGGAGAAGGUGGAAGGUCCAGGCUGCUCCUAUUUGCAGCACAUUCAGAUUGAAACAGGUGCCAAAGUCUUCCUGCGGGGCAAAGGUUCAGGCUGCAUUGAGCCAGCAUCUGGCCGAGAAGCUUUUGAACCUAUGUAUAUUUACAUCAGUCACCCCAAACCAGAAGGCCUGGCUGCUGCCAAGAAGCUUUGUGAGAAUCUUUUGCAAACAGUUCAUGCUGAAUACUCUAGAUUUGUGAAUCAGAUUAAUACUGCUGUACCUUUACCAGGCUAUACACAACCCUCUGCUAUAAGUAGUGUCCCUCCUCAACCACCAUAUUAUCCAUCCAAUGGCUAUCAGUCUGGUUACCCUGUUGUUCCCCCUCCUCAGCAGCCAGUUCAACCUCCCUACGGAGUACCAAGCAUAGUGCCACCAGCUGUUUCAUUAGCACCUGGAGUCUUGCCGGCAUUACCUACUGGAGUCCCACCUGUGCCAACACAAUACCCGAUAACACAAGUGCAGCCUCCAGCUAGCACUGGACAGAGUCCGAUGGGUGGUCCUUUUAUUCCUGCUGCUCCUGUCAAAACUGCCUUGCCUGCUGGCCCCCAGCCCCAGCCCCAGCCCCAGCCCCCACUCCCAAGUCAGCCCCAGGCACAGAAGAGACGAUUCACAGAGGAGCUACCAGAUGAACGGGAAUCUGGACUGCUUGGAUACCAGCAUGGACCCAUUCAUAUGACUAAUUUAGGUACAGGCUUCUCCAGUCAGAAUGAGAUUGAAGGUGCAGGAUCGAAGCCAGCAAGUUCCUCAGGCAAAGAGAGAGAGAGGGACAGGCAGUUGAUGCCUCCACCAGCCUUUCCAGUGACUGGAAUAAAAACAGAGUCCGAUGAAAGGAAUGGGUCUGGGACCUUAACAGGGAGCCAUGAUUAUCCAGCCAAGAAGAUGAAAACUACAGAGAAGGGAUUUGGCUUGGUGGCUUAUGCUGCAGAUUCAUCUGAUGAAGAGGAGGAACAUGGAGGUCAUAAAAAUGCAAGUAGUUUUCCACAGGGCUGGAGUUUGGGAUACCAAUAUCCUUCAUCACAACCACGAGCUAAACAACAGAUGCCAUUCUGGAUGGCUCCCUAGGAAACAGUGGAACAGAGUUUUGACCCUCAGUGACUCUUCUUAGCAAUAAUGCAUGCAUUUGAUUUAACAAGACUCUGGGGCCUGUGCUGGGAACCAUCUGGACCUUUGCAGAAGUUAGAGAUUCAGUGCCCCCCUUUCUUAAAGGGGUUCCUUAACAACCACAAAAAUCCUUAUUUCUGCAGUGGCAUAGAAUCUGUUAAAAUUUAAUUAGAAUCACAAAUUUAUCUCAGAAGCUUUUUAACAGUUGGUGAAAUGUGCUUGUCCAACAAAGCAUCCUAACAGGGUCGUUCCCAUACACAUUUGACCUGGUCAGCCUUUUCCAGGUGAAUAGCCCCAGUUCUGACAUAAAGAAAGUUUUAUUUGUAUUUUACUACUGUUUGGUCAAUUUUGAUAUAUAACUGGUUACAAACAGAGCCUUACUAUUUAUUAGUGGGGAAAUGAUUUUAAGACCGUCCUUUUCAGUAUUUAAUUCUGACAGAUCUGCAUCCCUGUUUUGUUUUGGAUUAUUUCUGUUUUGGAAAAUGCUGUCUCAUUUAAAACUGUUGGAUAUAGCUGGAUCCUGGAUAGGAAAAUGAAAUUAUUUUUUCAUUGUGUUUUUUAAUUGGGGUGAUCCAAAGCUGGCACCUUCAGGCACAUUGGUCUCAUAGCCAUUACUGUUUUUAUUGCCCUUCUAAGAUCCUGUCUUCAGCUGGGUCAGAGAAAACUUCUUGACUAAAACUGGUCAGAACUCAUCACAGAAAUGAAAUACAGUGGUCUCUCUCUCCCAGAACUGGUUGCAGCUAAAACAGAGAGAUCUGACUGCUGGCUAUAGGAUUUUGGACUUAAUGACUGAAAUUGCAAAUUGUCCUUUUUCUUGGCAUUACAGAUUUUGCCAAAAUAACUUUUUGUAUCAAAUAUUGAUGUGUGAAAGUGAAGGAGCUAGUCUGCUGAACCAGGAAUAGUUUGAGAUAUUGAACUGUCAUUUUUGCACAUUUGAAUACUUUGCAGGCUGGCUUUGUAUAAACUUAUCCUCUGGUUUCCUAUAUGUUGUAAAUAUUUAGACCAUAAUUUCAUUAUAAAUAAAUCUAUAAAUAUUC